AGAGCGCGCUCGGACCUCCUUCCCGGCGGCAGCUACCGAGAGUGCGGAGCGACCAGCGUGCGCUCGGAGGAACCAGAGAAACUCAGCACCCCGCGGGACUGUCCGUCGCAAAAUCCAACAUGAAAAUCCUCGUGGCCUUGGCAGUCUUUUUUCUUGUCUCCACUCAGCUGUUUGCAGAAGAAAUAGGAGCCAAUGAUGAUCUGAAUUACUGGUCCGACUGGUACGACAGCGACCAGAUCAAGGAGGAACUGCCGGAGCCCUUUGAGCAUCUUCUGCAGAGAAUCGCCCGGAGACCCAAGCCUCAGCAGUUCUUUGGAUUAAUGGGCAAACGGGAUGCUGAUUCCUCAAUUGAAAAACAAGUGGCCCUGUUAAAGGCUCUUUAUGGACAUGGCCAGAUCUCUCACAAAAGACAUAAAACAGAUUCCUUUGUUGGACUAAUGGGCAAAAGAGCUUUAAAUUCUGUGGCUUAUGAAAGGAGUGCAAUGCAGAAUUAUGAAAGAAGACGUUAAUAAACUACCUAACAUUAUUUAUUCAGCUUCAUUUGUGUCAAUGGGCAAUGACAGGUAAAUUAAGACAUGCACUAUGAGGAAUAAUUAUUUAUUUAAUAACAAUUGUUUGGGGUUGAAAAUUCAAAAAGUGUUUAUUUUUCAUAUUGUGCCAAUAUGUAUUGUAAACAUGUGUUUUAAUUCCAAUAUGAUGACUCCCUUAAAAUAGAAAUAAGUGGUUAUUUCUCAACAAAGCACAGUGUUAAAUGAAAUUGUAAAACCUGUCAAUGAUACAGUCCCUAAAGAAAAAAAAUCAUUGCUUUGAAGCAGUUGUGUCAGCUACUGCGGAAAAGGAAGGAAACUCCUGACAGUCUUGUGCUUUUCCUAUUUGUUUUCAUGGUGAAAAUGUACUGAGAUUUUGGUAUUACACUGUAUUUGUAUCUCUGAAGCAUGUUUCAUGUUUUGUGACUAUAUAGAGAUGUUUUUAAAAGUUUCAAUGUGAUUCUAAUGUCUUCAUUUCAUUGUAUGAUGUGUUGUGAUAGCUAACAUUUUAAAUAAAAGAAAAAAUAUCUUGAA